ACUCCCUCUCUCUUCUCCACUAUGGACAGAGCCUCCACUGAGCUGCUGCCUGCCCGCCACAUACCCAGCUGACAUGGGCACCGCAGGAGCCAUGCAGCUGUGCUGGGUGAUCCUGGGCUUCCUCCUGUUCCGAGGCCACAACUCCCAGCCCACAAUGACCCAGACCUCUAGCUCUCAGGGAGGCCUUGGCGGUCUAAGUCUGACCACAGAGCCAGUUUCUUCCAACCCAGGAUACAUCCCUUCCUCAGAGGCUAACAGGCCAAGCCAUCUGUCCAGCACUGGUACCCCAGGCGCAGGUGUCCCCAGCAGUGGAAGAGACGGAGGCACAAGCAGAGACACAUUUCAAACUGUUCCCCCCAAUUCAACCACCAUGAGCCUGAGCAUGAGGGAAGAUGCGACCAUCCUGCCCAGCCCCACGUCAGAGACUGUGCUCACUGUGGCUGCAUUUGGUGUUAUCAGCUUCAUUGUCAUCCUGGUGGUUGUGGUGAUCAUCCUAGUUGGUGUGGUCAGCCUGAGGUUCAAGUGUCGGAAGAGCAAGGAGUCUGAAGAUCCCCAGAAACCUGGGAGUUCAGGGCUGUCUGAAAGCUGCUCCACAGCCAAUGGAGAGAAAGACAGCAUCACCCUUAUCUCCAUGAAGAACAUCAACAUGAAUAAUGGCAAACAAAGUCUCUCAGCAGAGAAGGUUCUUUAAAAGCAACUUUGGGUCCCCAUGAGUCCAAGGAUGAUGCAGCUGCCCUGUGACUACAAGGAGGAAGAGAUGGAAUUAGUAGAGGCAAUGAACCACAUGUAAAUUAUUUUAUUGUUUCAUGUCUGCUUCUAGAUCUAAAGGACACUAGCAUUGCCCCAGAUCUGGGAGCAAGCUACCAACAGGGGAGACUCUUUCCUGUAUGGACAGCUGCUGUGGAAAUACUGCCUGCUUCUCCCACCUCCUCAGAGCCACAGGAAAGAGGAGGUGACAGAGAGAGAGCAAGGAAAGUGAUGAGGUGGAUUGAUACUUUCUACUUUGCAUUAAAAUUAUUUUCUAGCCUGCA